UUAUUUCCCCCCGAACUUAAGAUGGCCGCAGGUGGGCCCGGAACAGCCCUCAUGGCAAACGUCUCAGAGCGUUUUUCCACUCUGAAAAUCGCGGAGACCGCGCCUGAGCCACAGUCCAGUUUUUAAGGCCUUGGUGUCAGGCCGUUUUGCUGACGAGAAAGCCUGCUGCUGGUGACAAGAUGGAACUGGGGCUGUGUUUGUUUCCCAGGACGGUCGCACAAACUUAGCAUUUUGGUUUAUCUAACCGAGCGCAUCCAUGUUCCCAAAGAUCAUGUCUGUUAGCCCUUUUGACAGCAGAUUAAAUUUUCCUCCUGAAAGGUCACACUGUCCCAAAGCUUUCAGAAAAAGUCAACGCACCUCUUGCUUUUUCCUCCAAAGUAUGUUAUGUUAAGUUUCGUGAUCCAUCAAGUGUUGGCGUGGCCCAGCAUCUAACUAACACGGUUUUUAUUGACAGAGCUCUGAUAGUUGUUCCUUGUGCAGAAGGUUGGUAUCUCGCUUUUUUUCCUCUUAUUUGAAUUUCUGUCCUGUCUGUUAUUGCCUUUAGCUUUCCUAGAGAUUGGCAAGUAGACAGUACUCUUGGUGUGUGUGUGAAAGUAAGAAUGAAAUUUGGAGGAGGUAAACCUUUUUACCUAAUAGUAAUAUUAAAAUGGUUAAUUUAUGACAUGUACAUUUGAGGUUUUACAAUUUAACAUUCAUUGGCUUCUGGUUUGCUUUGGCUUUCUGUAGUCAAUUUGCAGAUUGCAAAGAAAGCUUUCUGAAAUUAAAAAAUAAUUGAUAUGGGAAAUUAUUUUAAAUGCAUAAACAAGCAUUUACCUUGUGUGUUCAAUAUUAAUACUAUUACAAAUGAAAAUAGUGUACACAUUUUGGCAAAUUGGGGUUAAGUGAUAUUUAUAAGAAAAUAUUUGUAAUUUAUACUUUCAAGUACACUCUUAAGGUAAUUUACCUUAAUUGUUACUAUGAGAUCAUUAUUUUAUAUUCAAUGUAAUUGUUUGCUUUGCAACUGGAAUUUAAUGUUUUCUUUUACUGGCCCCAAAAAGGGGCAGGAGGAGUGUUGGAAAAAAAGGAAAGCAAUUUUCCAAAGCCUCCAUGAAGGAAGUAGUUGUUGAAGAUAGGAACAAAGGCCUUAAAGUAUCCAUUAAAUUUUAUGACCUAAACUGCUUUAAGAACUAAUUAUUACUAAUAUUUUUUAGUAACUUCUGUUUACAGAGCCACUCACGUAUAAUAGACUGUGCUGAAUUUUGACACUUCUGGUGUAUAAUUAACUUUUAUUCAGAGCACUGACUAGCAUGUGUACAGGAUUUUAGAAUUGGGUUAUUAUAAAUUAAAAUGUCUUAAAGUAGAUUUUCUCUGGUGGAUGAUUGAAACUGUUUUAAACAUAAAGGUUUAUGGAAAACAGUUUGAUGGGCUUUCAUAUGUAAUUUUUAAAACCUCUUUUAGUGGCCAGGCUGACAUUAAAAUAAUAUAUAAUAAGCAGUUUGCUGCACUUUAAAGGUUUUAUGCUUAUUUCAGAAUGCCUGUUCUGGGAUGUCAAAAACAUUACAGUCUAAUACAGUGAGUACCAGGCUCGUAUUUUUUAAGUCCCAGAAUAGGACAUUCUCAGUAUUUUUCAGAUAAAUUUGGAAGUGUCUUUCCCAUGCUUGGGGGUUAGAGUGGGUAGGGAAGAUAAAAAUGGAUUAAAGUUAAUUAUUGGCCAAAUGUAUCUUUAUCUGCUGAUCUGUAAGGCUACAGUAAGCCCCAAAUUGGUGAGGUGGGAAAGGAGCUGGUGAAUGGUUUCGUUCUACAAACUUUGUAGUGAAAUUUCAUACUGAGAAACUGCAUGGGAAAAAAGAAAUCAGGUAAAAGGUUUAUUAAACUGGAAUAUUAAUUAUAUCAGAAAAUUAAUACCACCAAUAACACUGGGUCUUUUAUUGUGUUAGCUUAUUACUGAAUUGGAAGGAAGAAUUUUAUCAGUGUUGCUUGGUUGAAACCUGCUUUAUUCCCAUAGAAUCUUUCAUAUAUCUGAGAAGCCCUACUGUAUUUUGUUAUAAAUGUUCAAGAUGAUGGGCGUGUAGAUGUCCCUUUUAUUGUUUAUUUUACUUGAUAGAGAUGAAUAAAUGCACAGUCAGAUGUACCUUUUUAGUGUUUUUAAUAUUACAACUUGGACAGUUUUACUGUUUUUGAACAGAAAAAUUUAAGCAUACUUUUAUUGCAAUUUAGUUAUAAGUAAGUAAAUAUUUUGAAACACUAACCUACAGUUGGUAUUGGUGAAACAUUCAGAUAUACGUUUUUCAUUAGUUGUAUUAAAUACGGCAGAGAUGAAUUUAUGGAACCUCGAGAAUUUCACAGUGAGCUGUUAAAAUACUGAUUAUGCACUACAAGCAAAGAAAUAGUGCAUUAUUGUACUAAAAAAGAUAGCAGAGUGAGUGUGAAAUAACCAAAGAAAAGUAUUCCAGUGGAGUAAGUUCUGUAAGAGGAGAUGUGCUGUGGUGCUGUAAGCAAGCAGUGUUCUGUUGACCUCACUGAAUGCAUCCUUUCCUUGAUGUUGAACAAACAGCAUCAUGACAUAAGUGAGAAAAACCAUAGAAAAAAAUUUAAGAAGUUUUUUCAGUUUCUUUGAAUUGCUGUUUUUUAGUGUAGACAGUAAUGUGAGAAGAUCCUAAGUUGUAAAAGUAACAUUUGAUGUGUAACAGUUUCAUGCAUAUUAAGCCUUAGCCUUUGUUAAUAAAACAUGCCAUUUCAAAAUAAAAUAUGCUUUCAUUAUACUUGUCCAAAUAUGACCUCUUUUUGUUGUUGCGUGCAUUUCAGAUUUCUUUUUAUAAAUGUUAACACGUAGAAAAAGAUACGGUCAAACAUAACAAGGGUGUCAGCCUAAUCAUCAGUCAUAACUUUAUGUCCACAUUUUCUGGUAGAUGGAUUUUGACUAUUAAUUUGGUUUUGUAUGUUUUCUCUAUGUGAUAUUUGUGCAUUAUUAGAUGACUAGACUGGCCAAGGCAGACCUGUUACACUUGCCUGAGUUAGGCAUUGUUUGCCAUGCCACUAAACCUGCCGUCAAGUGAAACCUUCAUUGGGGAAAUGAGAUCGGAGUCUGAACCGCAGAAGAUGGACGCCCUGUCUCUGUUUUUUAUUGUUUUACUUUAAUUUCAUUUCUUUUUCUUUAUUUUGUCCCUUUUUUUGUUUUUGUUUUUGUUUUUGUUUUGUUAAAUCUCUUUCACUUUAACUUGUGAGCUGGUUUUCCCAGUUCUUUGUAAAUGGUAUUUCAUUAAGGGUUCAUAACGUGUUGCAAAUUAUAUUGGGAGAUGAUUAGUAGAGCUCAACCUUAAGAUAAAGCAAAUUUUCAUGUGGUAAAUUAGGAUACAGUGUUGUGAAGCUCAUUGUGAGUCUUAAUUUGUGUGUAUGGACUCAUAAGGUACAUUUUAUUCUUGAAACAUUAAAACACUGAUAAGUAUCUCAGGAACACUUUCUGAUCUCAGCGCAACAUUUUUCUAGUUUUUUUCCCCCCUAGUCUACAUCUCUCAUAAAAACUGAUAGCUUCUAAUUUUUGUCCUUCCCCCUGGAAUUUUAGGCAUACAAAAUCAUCAAGGAAAAUAAGUAAAUAUAACAAUCUGGGAGUAAAGAAGAGCCUUUCAUUUUUAUGAUGGUUAUUUAUCAUAUAACUUAUUUCCUUGACUUAUGAAGACUUUUUGUUGCCUAUGUGGGGAAUGGAUAUUUGAGAAACUUAAGUAUUUGCAUGUAGGUUUUUGUUAGCUUGAAUUUUUUGUUGAAUAUUUUUCAGAGGUUACUAGCUUCUAAAUGGAUUCUGAGAUUAGGACUAUAAUACUGUGAGAGAUGUUUUCCUCAGUUGACUUUGAGGAGUAUAGUUUGGGAAAAAUGCUAAAUGCUUAUUUGUUUUAUACUUUUAUAAGCUCUGUUAUUUGGAGGGUAAAUUUGGUAGAAUUCUAUCUUGGAAAUUAAGCAAUGGAGCUUUUUCUUAAAGUACUUUUGCCAUUACCUUUAGGUAAUUAGAAUAAGUAUAUAGAGUAAUUAGAAUGGUAAUUGAAAGUUAAUUUAUUAAAAAAUGUGCUUAUAGUGGAUUUAUACAUUUAUAGUAGUAUACUAUAUUUAUAGUAGUAUACUCUUUUGAAAGGCAGUGGGAGAGUUUGACAACCUACUGAUACUUAAGCUGAAAGUGAAAGACUUCAUAAUACUAAGUAGUCAACUUUUGGCCAGUGUUGAAUACCCUUUUUGUUUGUAUAGUCUUUCUACAAUGUCUUCAAUAGGUAGUUUUACUUAUUAAAGGACAAGUAAUAUUAAAUUUGGGACAUUACUAGAUUAGAACUCUGAGUUUCCUUAGGUGCAUACAUUAAGGUAGUGACGAUGGAGUUUCUGCCUCAAAACCUCAAUUUAUCAAGAAUGUUCAGGUUUUACAAACCUUUUGAGAUAAUACCAAUUUAUAACAGAUAAAACAGGUGAAAUCAAUAUAAAUAGUAUAGUGUAUAUGUGGGUAUAUAUAAAUACAUGUGUUAAUACCAAUAACUAAUACAUAUAAAGCAGAUUAUUGUUAUUUGAUGUUUUCAGUAAGGCCUACCUGCCUUUUGUUGAUGCAUGUUAAGAAAUCUGUUCUCCAGAAUUUUCACUGAAAUAAUAAAGAUAACUUUGUUUUUGAAAGUAAUAAAGUAAUAUAAACUUAGAUGCUGCAAAGGUAGAAAAUAGUAGGUUUUAUUUGCUUCCUAUAAAUAAGGCAUAGCCAUUAUUUAAAUCAAGUUUUAAAUUCCAACUUGAGUUCCAUCCAUGUUUAAAGAUAUAUUCAGAUAAUAUUGUUUAGGGAUUUAUCUCUGCACAUGUGGUUGUUUUAAAUAUUUUUACAACUGAAACCAGGCAUGGUGCUUGUGGAAAUUUACUGCAUAUGCUAUAUUUCAGUUUAGCAUGAUUUUGUGCAUUGUCUUUUAAAACACUUUUGGAGAAUUAAUAAUAGAAAUGCUUUACCAGCUACCACAUGAGUGUUCUUCUAAAUAUAUCCACAUGUAGUCAACUAUUUAAGAAUUUUUUUUUUUUUUUUUUGCCUAAGGGGAUAAGGAAAAAUAAUGUGAAAGUUGCAGUCCUUAUCAGAAGUAAUUGAUUAGAAUUCAGCAAUGAAUAUGCCAAAUCGUACUUAUUUCAGAGUAAGUUUUUCAUUUUUUUAGGUUGUAGGGAGUUUUUUUCCUACUGAGUGUUAUUAGAUUAUUUUAAUGUUACUAUUGUUAUUAGGCAAUUAAAAUGUUUUUAAGCAAGCUUUAAGGCAUUAACCUCCCCCUUCAGAUAAGUAUACAUAAAUUGGUUCUAAAAGUUAAUAAGAAGUUUUCUGAAACCAGGGAACUUUUUUUUUCCUGAAACAUUUUUAGUAGUUUCCCAAGGCAUAUUUUUUGGAACUGAGUUCUUUUAGGCAUCUCUGAUGUUGGUGAGAUGCUUUAUUAACUGAAUGGAUGUAGGCUUCCUUUUACGUUGAAGUUGAUUACAUGGAGUAAGUUUUUGUUUUCUAUUUGAAAUUAAAUGGAAUCUGUUGGAGGGUUAUCAAAAUUGUUUGCAUCACAAAUAGGUAGUUUCAGUAACAGGAUAGGGGCACUCAUUAAGAAAUUUCAAUUCGCACAUAUUUGUUUUUUCUUUUUCUUUUUUUUGACUAAUUUGGUUAUUUGCCAUUUCUGGGGAUUAAACUUUAAAAAAUGUUCUUCUUUUCUGUAUCUGAUGUUCUGUGUGCUAUUAGUGAUGCAGCCAACACGAACGGUUGUCAUGUGUAACACAACUUUCGAUCACCGCGAAAACACCGUCCUGGGAAAGCGUCCAUGCUUGAUAUCGUUUGGUUCAUGAACAUUAAGUUUCCAGUACAGGUGACCCAUAGCUCAAAGUGUUAAAUAAUUGUCUACAUUAUUCAAUUUUUAAAAUAAUAUUCCAUUAAUGAGAUUGUUAAUAUUUGAAGUUUUGCUCACUUUUAUUUUUCCUAGUAGAGCAGGAUAAAAGGAAAGACUUAAGUUCUUAUUUAUUUCUUUAUACAGAUCUGAUAGAUAGAUUCAUUUAUUAUUAUUAUUUUUUAACUGCAAGGGUAAUUGUAAAAUCAUAGUGUAAAGUUUGUGUGGUGUUUCUGCUUUUUGUAAUGUUUGGAACUUGCCUCUGCAGGUAAAAUCCCAGAGGAAUCCAAAGCCCUCUCUUUAUUGGCUCCUGCUCCAACCAUGACAAGUCUGAUGCCUGGUGCAGGAUUGCUUCCAAUACCGACCCCAAAUCCUUUGACUACUCUUGGUGUUUCACUUAGCAGUUUGGGAGCUAUACCAGCAGCAGCACUAGACCCCAACAUUGCAACACUUGGAGAGAUACCACAGCCACCACUUAUGGGAAACGUGGAUCCUUCCAAAAUAGAUGAAAUUAGGAGAACGGUUUAUGUUGGAAAUCUGAAUUCCCAGACAACGACAGCUGAUCAACUACUUGAAUUUUUUAAACAAGUUGGAGAAGUGAAGUUUGUGCGGAUGGCAGGUGAUGAGACUCAGCCAACUCGGUUUGCUUUUGUGGAAUUUGCAGACCAAAAUUCUGUACCAAGGGCCCUUGCUUUUAAUGGAGUUAUGUUUGGAGACAGGCCACUGAAAAUAAAUCACUCCAACAAUGCAAUAGUAAAACCCCCUGAGAUGACACCUCAGGCUGCAGCUAAGGAGUUAGAAGAAGUAAUGAAGCGAGUACGAGAAGCUCAGUCAUUUAUCUCAGCAGCUAUUGAACCAGAGUCUGGAAAGAGCAAUGAAAGAAAAGGCGGUCGAUCUCGUUCCCAUACUCGCUCAAAAUCCAGGUCUAGCUCAAAAUCCCAUUCUAGAAGGAAAAGAUCACAAUCAAAACACAGGAGUAGAUCCCAUAAUAGAUCACGUUCAAGACAGAAAGACAGACGUAGAUCUAAGAGCCCACAUAAAAAACGCUCUAAAUCAAGGGAGAGACGGAAGUCAAGGAGUCGUUCGCAUUCACGGGACAAGAGAAAAGACACUCGAGAAAAGAUCAAGGAAAAGGAAAGAGUGAAAGAGAAAGACAGGGAAAAGGAGAGAGAGAGGGAAAAGGAACGUGAAAAAGAAAAGGAACGGGGUAAAAACAAAGACCGGGACAAGGAACGGGAAAAGGACCGGGAAAAAGACAAGGAAAAGGACAGAGAGAGAGAACGGGAAAAAGAGCAUGAGAAGGAUCGAGACAAAGAGAAGGAAAAGGAACAGGACAAAGAAAAGGAACGAGAAAAAGACAGAUCCAAAGAGAUAGAUGAAAAAAGAAAGAAGGAUAAAAAAUCCAGAACACCACCCAGGAGUUACAAUGCAUCGCGAAGAUCUCGUAGUUCCAGCAGGGAAAGGCGUAGGAGGAGGAGCAGGAGUUCUUCCAGAUCGCCAAGAACAUCAAAAACCAUAAAAAGGAAAUCUUCUAGAUCUCCGUCCCCCAGGAGCAGAAAUAAGAAGGAUAAAAAGAGAGAAAAAGAAAGGGACCACAUCAGUGAAAGAAGAGAGAGAGAACGUUCAACGUCUAUGAGAAAGAGUUCUAAUGAUAGAGAUGGGAAGGAGAAGUUGGAGAAGAACAGUACUUCACUUAAAGAGAAAGAGCACAAUAAAGAACCAGAUUCAAGUGUGAGCAAAGAAGUAGAUGACAAGGAUGCACCAAGGACUGAGGAAAACAAAAUACAGCACAAUGGGAAUUGUCAGCUGAAUGAAGAAAACCUCUCUACCAAAACAGAAGCAGUAUAGGACCGACAAGUGUACCUCUGCACUCAAUGCUGGAAUCAAAUCCAAAGCUUUUAAUUCUCUCAACAAGAUGUAAACAGGAAAGAAAUCUAGUUGAGCAUGAAGAUAGGAUCUAACAGCUUUUCCAGUUGUUAGAUGACUUUGUGGCCAUCUUGUUAUUGAGUAAGAAAAUAAAGCAUGGACAUCAUGAAAAUAACAGAUGUUACCCAAACUCAUCUUCUAAAAUCUGUGCAUUUCCAUGGUGGCUGACACACUUGUCAUGUGGUCUGUUAGUGUUUGCCAAGAACCAUUGCAAAUAAAUUGAACAUCAAAGAUCCAAGUUUGUACUAUCCCUAAAGACUGGAGAUAAGCAUUGGAGGCUCUUUUAAAAAAUGCUAGUUACUGAAUUUUGUAUUGUUUUACUUUUUUUUUUAUUUCAAUAUAUACAGUUUGAUGAUGUGCUUGAAAUUGGUGCAAAUAUAUACACACCCUUGUAAGUGCAAAGUAUGUAAGAAGUUUUAACAUUUACUUCACAGGACUUGUGAUUGUGUUAAAUUCUCACUAUUGUGUUUUCUUUUGCUCACUGUUUAGGACAAUUUUUCUUUAAAAUAGUUUUGCAGAUUAAAAUUGCUUAAAUAAGUGGAUUAAAAAACUGACAAUGCAUGCUACUGUUCUCUUUCAAAAGGAAGAGCAACCGUGUUGAAUACUAAUAAUGAUGAAUUAGUAUUCAGUGUUUAGAAUCAUUGGGACUACCCACAAAGUGAGCAUUUCUUUUUAAAUUUUCUUGACAUUUCCAAGCUUAUUAUGAAUAAUAUUGCAGUGUGUCUUGUCAGCUGUAGGUGGCAAAGGUGCCCUUAUAAAAAAGGAAACUGGCUUUUCAAAAUGGGCUAUGGGAGCACAAGCUGAAGCUUUAGUGCCUUCUACAAUGUGGUAUACUGUUUUCUAGAAUUUUAUAUGUGCUAGUCAUUCUCAAUUCAUAUGGAAUCUAGAUGGAUAUUUCAUGCAUACCCAUAGAGAAGUGUGUAAGUGAUAUGUCAGAAGAGCUUCUUACUGAUUUCACCUAAAAUGAGAAGGAAGUCCUGUUUUCAAGAAUGACAUUAGAGUCAUGCAGCUUUGGGACCAUCAGUUUUAUACUGUGAUAAUUGAAAAUGAAACAUGUUCUUAUUUUCCUUAAAUUGAAGAAAACCCUUUAGUUGUCUACAUUGGAUGGCCUUAUUACCUCUCAAUCAUCUUUUCAUAAAUGAUGUGCAGAAAUUGUACUUAAGGACUUAGGAGUAUAUGGGAGGUUAUUGGUUUUAUGUUUAAGGAUACGUUUACUUGAGUUUAAGAUACAGGUCAUCCAUCAUUCUUAGGCUCACUUUUUACAGAAAGUAUGCAAAUAGUAAAGUGACAGCACUGCUAAUGUUUUUCCCCAGUACUAUAACUUGUGGUUUCUGAACUCAUUAUUGUUGUAUUUCCAAAAAAGUAAUACCUUUUAAUUAGUGUAUUAAAAGUUAAGUAUAAUUAUUUUAAUGCAAUCUAAUACAAUCAGAUUACUCAGUUGCCUUACCUCAUGGGAAGAGUUACUUUUUUAGAUCUAAAAAGCUGAAUAGCAUGUUAGUUACUUGGUUUCAACUUGAGUUUUCUUUUAAUGUUAAUAAGAUUGAAACUUUAGUAUUUAGUGGGGAAUGGAAAGAGUUGCCCUUGUUGCAAGUAAUGAAGCCUGAUUUGAUUAUGAAGCUGCUUAAUCACUCUUCAUGUGUUCAGAAUUACUGUUUUUUUUGUUUGUUUUUCCUUUUUGUCACUGUGUACAUUAAAAUUUUGGAAGAUGCUUUACUAUGUAAAGUAUAGAUGGUCAUUUUAAUCAUUCAGCCACAUACGGUUGGCUGGUAAACAGCUUAUUCUGAUACAAGAAUGCUUGGGUGCAUAUGGAAAGAUUGUGAAAGAGUGUGUCUUGCAUCAACAGCUGUCUUAUUUAUGAUAUAUAAGUAGAAAUAGAGCAAAUGUUGGAAUCUGUUAUUUUUAGUACCAUGUCUUUAAUAAAGCUAAGUAUUUUAGAGGAAAAUGUUUGUUUAUGCAUUUCAAAAAAGCAUUUUAGUUUUAUCCUGCUCAUUUUAGUUGUCAUAGAGAUUGUUGUGACGUGGAGAGUGCAUGUUUGUGUGGUGUCUAUAAAACAAGUCAUUUAAAGUAUGAGUGUUUUCUUGUACUCUGGACCUAUUACAUGUUUCUUUAUGUUGGUAAUUAACAUUUAAUUUGGUUCUUGCUGCUAAUUAUUUUCUCUGCUGAUAUUUAUUAAGCUUUAAAAUAAUCGUACUAUAAUCUUGAAACACUGAUUUGUAAAAACUAAGAAUGAGUAGGAAUACAAGAGAUCUGGAGGAACAAAUCAGAUUGUUAUUAGGGUUUGACUUUUUUUUUACAUGGGCUUAUGGAAGCAAGGCAUUCUAGGGUCUAGAGGGAUGUGUGUGUGUGCUUGUGUGUCCAUGUGUGCGCAUGCGCACGUGUGUAUCUGUUUGAGACAUACUUUCUCUGUUCACUUAAAAGAGCUCAUGUUUUCAUUUGUUUAUUCUUUUCUUUCAGGGUAUUUUGUUUUUUUCUUUAAGACUUCUUUUUUUAAAUCCCAGGUAGAUGUUGUCAGAUAAACUUGAGGUAAGGCCAAGAAGACAGACAUUUUAUGCUUCAUACUUUCUGUAAUUAUCUUUUGUAGCUUGAUUACAUAGAGUACCCUCUCUUCCUUAAGUUGUAGUUGCUAUUUAUCAUUGUAGACAAAUUCUGUUGCCUUUCAGCAACGUAUGCUGAACUAGUAUCAUAAGAUGGUGCAUCAGUUCAUAAGCUAGUGCAUAAGUUUUGUGUCAAAACUUUUAAAUCCUGAAGUUCUGCAGUUAUCAUCUUAGUUAUUUUCUAUCUAAUUAGCUUAUAAUUGCAAACACUAGUCAGCUUGUGAUCUCUGUGUUUCAAGUUCUUUUCUUCACGAGGUUCAGUACCUGCUAUGUUGAUCUUUGGCAGUGCCAGAGGCUUAAAUUUUGACCUGCUCAAUUAAAAAUAAACACUGGCGUUUAUAAUGAAAAGGUUUUUUUGUCGGGGGGGGGGGGGUCAAGAGAAUUUAUUUUGUGAUAGUAAUAAUUUUCAAGACCUUCAGUCAUUCCUAUGUCUAUGUUGCUAUCUUUAUUUUAAAACUUAGAACCCUGAUCUAACUCCCUUCUCAAGUGAAGAUACUGUGUAGAUUCAAGAAUUAUAAUGUAGAGUAAUAGGCCUUUAAGUUUUUUUUUAAUCUGUUAGAAAUAAAGAGCAUGAUUUAAUUAUUGUUGAAUUAACAAUUAAAAUGAAUCCCUUUGGAGGGAUGGCAUUGAAUAACUUAUAAUUUCAGUGAAUCAUUUACGUUUUCAUUGGAAGACAGUAUCUGAUUUCAACUGGUGCGUUACGAAGUAGAGCCAUUCCCACAAAGUAAAUGUGCAGUGCCCAUGUUUCUUGUGUUUAAAUAUUUUUUAUUUUCACUACAUAUAUAUUAUUUUCUCAUGUUUAUUUACUAAUGUAAUUUUCACUUAAAAUUAGAUGUUUAUUUUCAAAUUUUAAAAGCUAGUGCUCUUAAAAGAGCUAAAUUAUAUUUCUGGAAGCAGGAGUUUAGUAUAAAUGUAAUAAAAUUUUAAAAUAAAAUUGACUUCCCUACUUAAUCUUGGGUUUGUGGGUGAGUUUGUUUUUAGUACACUCUUAUUGGUGGUUUUGCCUGAAGAGUAAUACAUUAUUAUUAUUACUUUUCUUUUUGAGACAGGGUCUCACUCUGUCACUCAGGCUGGAGUGCAGUGACACGAUCAUGGCUCACUGCAAUCUUGACCUUUCUCGGCAUGGAUGAUCCUCUCACCUCAGCCUCUUGAAUAGCUGGGACCACAGACAUGUGCCACCAAGCCCAGUUAAUUUUAGAAUUUUUUUUGUAGAGACAGGAUCUUGCCAUGUUGCCUAGACUGGUCUCAAACUCCUGGGCUCAAACAAUCUGUCUGCCUCAGCCUUCUAAAGUGCUGAGAUUACAGGUGUGAGGUACUGCACCUGGCAAUACGUUAUUUUAAAAGUAAACGCUAAGCCAUUUAUGACUUUGGUUAUAUUCAGUCAGUUGGAUUUAGUAACUAAUAACUAGCUUUCUUCCAUUCUAAGGUACUUUUAUAGUUUCUAGCAAUUAGUUUGUUACAAUUAGCUUAUAUCAGAUAUAACAGUUCUUAAUAUAAUGUUUAUAAAAGGUUUUAAGUCUGUUGCCUGAUUUUUAAAUUUAUAUCUAGUUAACAUUUUAAUUUUAAAAUUGCCAACUUUUGGGAGAUUUCACAUAUUUUACCUCUAUAUUUUAUUUUUCCAGGAUUGGUAUGGAGGAGUAGUACCUUCUAUUCUUGGUUUAUUUUUAUUUGCUAGACAUAAUUUCUUAACUACAUAUGUAAGUAUAAAUUCAUAAAAAUCACACUGAAAGAAUAGGUUGAUUUCAACCAUUUUGAGGGUACUGGUAGGUAACACACUGUUGGGGAAUAAACUAAAGAAUUUCUGAUUUCUACAAUAGAUUUAAGUAUGAAAUUUGAGUAUACUGUGUAGCUGUGUAGAUCAACUUAAUGCUUAAAAAAUUACCUCCUUAAUGAUUAGAUUAAUAGAACAGUGUUAGAUUAUCAAGGGAAGAGUUUGGAAUGUAAACAUAAACAUGCUGCAUAGGUGGUGGUUAUUUGUGAGUAGGACUACUUUUAAAUGGUACUAGUAAAGAUUUAUCAAACAAUGCUGCUAUUAUGUUGCUAUAUUUUUAAUAAAAUGAAAAUCUUAAAAUCUU